AGGAGGUCCGCGGGAGGAUGGAGCAGUGAGCGGGUCUGGGCGGCUGCUGGCAGCGCCAUGGAGACGGUACAGCUGAGGAACCCGCCGCGCCGGUGAGGGGCCACUGGCUAAGAGGACGGGCAUGGGGUCAGGGGAAGAAAAGGCGGGAACUGGUUGAGGGGAUACACCUGUGUGGGAGUCCCCGGAGCUAAGCGACCCAGCCGAUGGGGCACCUGCUGAGUGAGGGGGGGGACGUCUGGUGGGUGAGGGUCCGGCUGAGGGGAGCAUCUGCUAAGGAGGUUAGACUUGGGACCGGUUAGAGGGAGCACUCGCUGUGGUGAGACUGUGCUGAGGAACGUGGGGACAAGUUAGGGAGAGUACCUGCUGAGGCCGGGCCACUCGGGGGAACGCUAUCCAAGCAGGGACUCACGGAGGUGGGGGCGAAUGCUGAAGCAGGGUGAGAAUCUGUGAGGGAUCUCUUUAAGGGGGUGGAUCGAGAACUGGCCAAGAGGAAGGCCGGGUGGACUUUCUAAGGGUCUGAAGUCCCACUUGAGGGGUGCGGUGGGGGGAUCUGUGGAGGGGAAAAGCUUUGCGCCUAAGGCUGAAAGCAUGCGAGGAAAGGUUGAGGGUCUAGCAAGGGAGGGGAUGGUGGAGGGUAGCAUUUCAGAGGAUGCUGUUGGUGGUGUCCCCACUGUAGGAUGGCAUCUUUUAUUACUGAUGUUCAGUGUCUUCCUAAUGGUCUUCACAUCCUCCUCAGCUCUUCAGAACCUGACAUUGGGAGGUAGGUAAGGAAAUAAGAGGAUAUUUUCGAGAUGGGGAGACUGAGGUCCAGAGUAGUUGGGAAGUGUUUCCUUCUUUACUCCGGGUCACUGAACCCUGCCAGUCUGUGCCCUUUUCAGGCCUCAGUUGUUUUGUGAAUAUCAGCACCAAAUCCUAGUGGUACCUGGAAUUGCUUUAGUUCAAGAUCAGGAUGGUGGCUGAUCCUAGAAAAUCUCAACUCCUGGAUUUCCCUUGUGGACAUCCCGGGUCUUUUGCCACUCUACCACAUCUGGAGAAAAGUAGGGACUAGAGACCGAAGGAGUCAUGCUUCUCUGAGGUUCAGUGUGGUUACUUCUAUUUCACAGAGACGUCUGACUUCCUGCAGCAGAAUGAGCUCUAAAGAAGGAAGUGUUCAGGGUGUGGAAGUGCAGGGCAACCAAGAGGUGAAGAGAAGGGAUUGACUGCCUGGGCAGCACUCUUAGGGGUUGUUUGAGCUUGGGGAUGUUUGAGGUGCACAAACAUUGCAGAAGGCAAAUAGGUGGUUGGGAUGGGCUUUGGAUUCACCCUAGCGUAGUGUGCUGAGACUGUAAUAGUAAUGAUUAUUACACUCAUAUUGCACUUACCGGGUGCCAGGCACUGUUCUAAGUGCUUUCCAUGUGUCCUGCUGAAGCAUAUGAAAUUGCUGAUAUUUGACCAUUUUUGAACCAUAAAAACCUCAUUUGAACUCAUUUGAACCUCACAACAAUCCUGUGUGGUAGAUAUCCCUAUAUGUCUGUUUUACAGAUGAUAAAACUGAGAUACAGAGGGUAGUGAUUUGCUGGGAGAAGUCAUAGCAAGUAAGAGACAGAGCUAGGAUUUUAAUGUCUAUGGGGUCUGGUCCAAAGUCCAUGUUCUUUUUUUUUUUUUGAGACGGAGUCUCACUCUGUCGCCCAGUCUGAAGUGCAGUGGCGCAAUCUCGGCUCACUGCUACUUCCGCCUUCUGGGUUCAAGCGAUUCUCCUGCCUCAGCCUCCUGUGUAACUGGGACCACAGGUGCGUGCCACCACGCCUGGCUAAUUUUUUGUAGUUUUAGUAGAGACGGGGUUUCACCGUGUUAGCCAGGAUGGUCUCUAUCUCCUGACCUCGUGAUCCGCCCACCUUGGCUUCUCAAAGUGGUGGGAUUACAGGCGUGAGCCACCGGGCCCGGCCAUGCUCUUAACUGCCUCACUCUGAUGCCUCUCUAAAAGUACCCCUGUUUCACAGGUCUCUGUGUAUGUUAGCAGAUAUUUACUAUAGUACCAUAGUGAUCCAAUUAUGAAUGCACACUAGUUAUGUUUCUUUCUGAACUAUGUUCGUUCGUUCUUCUUGGUUUCUUUCUCCGAGGCCUUGGUUUAAUUGAAAAGAGGAUUAGGAAUCUGAGUUUUGUUUCCCCCUUUGCCUUGUCUUACAUAAUCUUGAGCAAAGGACUAAAGUUUCUUGGCAUGCUCAUUCCUGUACCUUUUGGAUUUUAAAAAAUGUAUUAAAAGCACAAGAGAAGAGCAUUGCAGGACUGGGUUCUGAAGUGGCUGGUGAUUCCCAGCUCAUUGUAACUAGUAGAUUGCCUAAUUUGAAGCAGAUCAAUUUUAUUAUCACGUGUAUCAGUUUAUCAGGACAAGACAAAGUGUCAUGGAGUGGGUGGUUUAAGCAACGUAAAUUUAUUCUCUCACUGUUCUGAAGGCUAGAGAUCUGAAAUCAAGGCAUUGUCAGAGUUGUUUCUUUUGACGCCUUUGCUUGACUCGUAGAUGGCCAUCUCCCUGUGUCUCCAUGUUCUUCCUUCUGUACCUGUCAGUGUCCUAAUCUCCUCUUAUAAGGACACCAGUCAUACUGGAUUAGGGCAUGCCCAUAUGACCUCAUUUUAUCUUAAUUACCUCUUUAAAGGCCUUGUCUCCAAAUACAGUCACAUUCUUAGGUGGUGGGUAUUAGGACUUCAGCAUAUGAAUUGGGGUAAGCUGGGGACACAGUUUUAUUAUGUAAGAUUUUGUCCAUUUAUCAUGUAUAGUUGUUGUAAUCCAUAUCAAAUUCUGUGUGGAAAAAGAAAUAGUUACACAUAAAAUGAACUUUAUGGGAGUUCUGAAAUGGGAGAAAGCUUUGAGAAUUAGCCAGACCUGUAAGUGACUACUUCAUAGACACCAUUACUUGUGUUUGGAAAGAUACAGGUGUCUUUUCAGAAAUUCAGAUGGCAUGUGUUUCCAAUAACCCCAGUGCAGGAAAUGCCCUUUGUGUUCGUGAGUUUGACAUUUGUGUGUGUGUGUGAUUAAGUGAUGACAGAUUGGUGUCUCAUAUAGGAGUUAAUAAUUUUAAAAAAUGAGUUGCCAUUAGAUUAAUGUUAUAGUGGAAGGCGUAGAGUGCAUUCCUGGGAUGCUGGCCAUCCACAUGGCCAUCUGACUUAGGAGAGGAGCAUCCACCAGUAUUUGGUCCAUGGAUGCUCUGUUGAUCAGGCUUGUUCAUUUAUGAGCAAGUGCUGAAACCGUCUGGAACCUGGGGAAGUCCCAGAUAAGAGAACUGUAUUAUCAGAGUCAGGCUGUUUUGGUAAUAGUGUUUUUUCUGUGAAGAGUCAUGGUAUAAAAUAUUAUUAUGAAUCACUUAUCAAAAUAUUUUUAUAGAAAUGUUGAUAAUUCAGUAAUACUUCUUAGGUGAAAUUCUGUUUUAUUGUGAUAAUUCAAAGAUUGCUGAUGAAAUUCGUGAUUCCCAUCAUUACAUUUGUGAAUCCAUUUCACAAAUAUAUUUUGACCACCUCUUGGUUAUCAGGCACCAGAGAUGUAAUAGCGCCUUAAGUUCAAGUUGUUUUUAAUAGCCCCGGAUCAAAAACAAACAAAAAAGCACUUAGAUUGUUUCAAAGAUGUAUUCGAGCCGUCAUAUGCUAAAUGACGAGUUAAUGGGUGCAGCACACCAGCAUGGCACAUGUAUACAUAUGUAACUAACCUGCACAUUGUGCACAUGUACCCUAAAACUUAAAGUAUAAUAAUAAUUAAAAAAAAAGAAAAAAAAAGUUUGUCAAAGUAUUAUCAGAGGUUUGCAGCUGUCUAUCUCAAGGCAGUGGCAAUUUCCUUUGUUAUGCUGUGGUCCCUGAAGUAGUUGAAAUAGUGACUUUUGCAUUUUGUAAACCACAGAGAGUCAACACUUCAAAGAAACAUACUUGAUCUUCCUUUGUAUAAGCUGUUUAUACAACUUUGAUUAUACUUGAGAAGUGAGGUAUUGUCCAAUGUUUAUACAAUUACAAUUCAGGACUUUACCAAAAAAACCCUGGCAUAUGAGAUGUUCGUUCUGACUUCUGAGUUUAUAGAAGUUUCAGUUCUGAAGUUUAAGAGGAGUUUCACUUCAUCCCUUUUCAUUUUGAAGGCAGCUGAAAAAGUUGGAUGAAGAUAGUUUAACCAAACAACCAGAAGAAGUAUUUGAUGUCUUAGAGAAACUUGGAGAAGGUCAUCGUCUUUUUGUAAGUUGGAAAAAUACUCUUUGGAAUCCAGCAAGAAAUCAAGCAGAGAAGGGAAGUAAAAAUGACACACCAGCUGUGCUGUGAAAAGACAAGUCCAAGAUGAAUCUGAAGACUGCCAGUUGACUGGCAUCAUUAAAGAGACGAGGUCUCACUGUGUUGCCCAGGCUGGUCUUGAACUCUUGGCCUUAAGUGAUCCUCCUGCCUCAGCCUCCCAAAGUGCUAGGAUUAGAGACGUGAACCACUGCACCUGGACAAAUUGCGUUUUAGAUCUAUGGAUGUCUUCUGCAAGGAAUGUGGAAAUUUCCCUAUGAAGAUAUCACCAGGGAGAAAACAAAGCUUCAGAUCUUUCUUCCCAUACUAUCACCUUAUUGUUCUUCUAAAUAAUACCAGAUUUCUGGUAUUUCUUGGAUUUCUGUUAUUCUGACUGAAUGAACCUAAGCAAGCCUCAUUUAACUAGGAAUAUUUUGAAGGAAGACCUUCACUGCACUUCUUUUCCAAACAUGUGACACAAUGCUAUUCUUUUUUUUUGAGAUUAAGUCUUGCUCUGUCACCAGGCUGGAGUGCAAUGUCACAAUCUCGGCUCACUGCAACCUCCGCCUCCCAGGUUCAAGCGAUUCCCCUGCCUCAGCCUCCUGAGUAGCUGGGACUAUAGGCACACACCACCACGCCCGACUUAUUUUUUGUAUUUUAGUAGAGAUGGGGUUUCACCAUAUUGGCCAGGAUGGUCUUGAUCUCGUGAUCUUGUGAUCUGCCUGCCUCAGCCUCCCAAAUUGCUGGAAUUACAGAUGUGAGCCACCACGCCUGGCCAAUGCUAUUCUUAAAUUGUUCGGGAGGAUGAAUGGUUUGUGAACUCUCACUGACUUGUAUCUUGUGAAAUGAGCUAUGGCUAAAAAAACUGUUGGAUUCUGGAGGCUGCAAUCAUUCUGUGUUAUGAGGAUCAUAUGGAUCUGUGGCAGAGUAGAGCCAAAGCUCCAGACCAGGAUGAGUGGAGAGCACUUGGGAAGUGUUUUCAAGUGGAGCCUAGCACCUUUUUUCUUCUACUUAAAGUUGUACACAUUGACUCAUUUGAAUUUUUAUCAUAGAAUGAUAACAAAAGCAUCUUGCCCAUGGUUUCAUAAAAAAUGAGUGCUAUUGUUAAGACUUGUAUCUGAUUAAUUUGGCCUCAGAUACUGUGGUAUUUCCAUUUUUCUACAUAGAUCCUUGCCUUGCAUGGCUUAUGUAAAACACCUACUUCUCCAUUCUCUGCUGUCAGUUGUAAUUCAUUGAAUCAUCUCAUUUUGUUGUAGGGAAUCAAGUUUUAAGGGACUUGCUUGUGAGUAUGAUUGCUGAAAUCUUCUAACCACCCCCUAUCCCUGCCUUCAGAUUACUGUAGAUGCAGUAUAUGGAAUCAGGAAUCUUAACUUCAUGUGAGCUAUUGGAGUUUUCCUUGCUAUCAGGAUGCAUAGGGAGGUCCUAUGGCAGCGUAUACAAAGCUAUUCAUAAAGAGACCGGCCAGAUUGUUGCUAUUAAGCAAGUUCCUGUGGAAUCAGACCUCCAGGAGAUAAUCAAAGAAAUCUCUAUAAUGCAGCAAUGUGACAGCCCUCAUGUAGUCAAAUAUUAUGGCAGUUAUUUUAAGAACACAGACUUAUGGAUCGUUAUGGAGUACUGUGGGGCUGGUUCUGUAUCUGAUAUCAUUCGAUUACGAAAUAAAACGUUAACAGAAGAUGAAAUAGCUACAAUAUUACAAUCAACUCUUAAGGGACUUGAAUACCUUCAUUUUAUGAGAAAAAUACACCGAGAUAUCAAGGCAGGAAAUAUUUUGCUAAAUACAGAAGGACAUGCAAAACUUGCAGAUUUUGGGGUAGCAGGUCAACUUACAGAUACCAUGGCCAAGCGGAAUACAGUGAUAGGAACACCAUUUUGGAUGGCUCCAGAAGUGAUUCAGGAAAUUGGAUACAACUGUGUAGCAGACAUCUGGUCCCUGGGAAUAACUGCCAUAGAAAUGGCUGAAGGAAAGCCCCCUUAUGCUGAUAUCCAUCCAAUGAGGGCAAUCUUCAUGAUUCCUACAAAUCCUCCUCCCACAUUCCGAAAACCAGAGCUAUGGUCAGAUAACUUUACAGAUUUUGUGAAACAGUGUCUUGUAAAGAGCCCUGAGCAGAGGGCCACAGCCACUCAGCUCCUGCAGCACCCAUUUGUCAGGAGUGCCAAAGGAGUGUCAAUACUGCGAGACUUAAUUAAUGAAGCCAUGGAUGUGAAACUGAAACGCCAGGAAUCCCAGCAGCGGGAAGUGGACCAGGACGAUGAAGAAAACUCAGAAGAGGAUGAAAUGGAUUCUGGCACGAUGGUUCGAGCAGUGGGUGAUGAGAUGGGCACUGUCCGAGUAGCCAGCACCAUGACUGAUGGAGCCAAUACUAUGAUUGAGCACGAUGACACGUUGCCAUCACAACUGGGCACCAUGGUGAUCAAUGCAGAGGAUGAGGAAGAGGAAGGAACUAUGAAAAGAAGGGAUGAGACCAUGCAGCCUGCGAAACCAUCCUUUCUUGAAUAUUUUGAACAAAAAGAAAAGGAAAACCAGAUCAACAGCUUUGGCAAGAGUGUACCUGGUCCACUGAAAAAUUCUUCAGAUUGGAAAAUACCACAGGAUGGAGACUACGAGUUUCUUAAGAGUUGGACAGUGGAGGACCUUCAGAAGAGGCUCUUGGCCCUGGACCCCAUGAUGGAGCAGGAGAUUGAAGAGAUCCGGCAGAAGUACCAGUCCAAGCGGCAGCCCAUCCUGGAUGCCAUAGAGGCUAAGAAGAGACGGCAACAAAACUUCUGAGCAAGGCCAGGCUGUGAGGGCCCCAGCUCCACCCAGGCUUUGGGUGAAUUCUGGAUGGCUUGCCUCAUGUUUGUUAGCCAGCACUUCUGCUCUGUCGUCUCUCCACAGCACCUUUGUGAACUCAGGAAUGUGCGCCAGUGGGAAGGGCUCUCUUGACAGUCAGCGUGCCAUCUUGAUGUGUGUAUGUACAUUGGUCAGGUAUAUUAUCUCAAAGGAUUUAUAUUGGCGCUUUUAACUCAGAGUUUUAAACCCCAGGAACAGAGACUCCUAGUUGAGUGAUAGCUGGGAAAGUUUUACAUUGUCUGUUUUUCUUCUCCCAAUAGCUUUCAAUUGUUCUUUCUGGAAGACUUUUAAAAAAAUAUAAAUAUGCAUAUAUAUAUAUAAAUUAUAAAUAGAUUCCCCACGCAGUGUGGUGGCAUCUCUGUACAGGUACAGUUUUAAACGGUUUGCCUCUUUUCUGUAAGAUUAUGGUACUGUGGAACAUGAGGGCAGAGGACACCGGGAGGCUGUUAGGGGGUCACUGAAUCCCAGGAGCCAACCUCCCCCUUUGCAGGGCUGCAUUUAAAAAUUAGGUUUGGGACAGUUCUUGUACCGUGGUUUCAGCCUUGUGUGGUCAUCACUGGCUUCUGGAGCUAUUGGUGAUGUCCAAGGGAAAGCUUUGAGAGUUUAUGUUUACUCUUUGAGUCCCAGGAGAAGCCUGGCACCCUCUUUGCAAAUUGGCCUUUGCUCUUUCAAUGCCUUUCAUCCAUCUCCACUCUCUCAACUGCCUAAAGUCACAGCACAGAUACUGCCCAGUGCCUUAAGAGGAGACAUGAUCUCUACCAGGGACUCUCAGCAAACACGGGACUGUGUUCAGUCCACAAAGGAAAAGCGUUUUUGAAGCUCUCAUUGUUCAUGUAAAAAUCAUACACGUGGCAUGUUGCUCCACAUUCCUUACACACAGGGGUAGAGGGGAUUGCUUUUGUGACCCACGUUCAAAUAUGUGACUGUUUUCUUUUCUCUUUUACUGCUAAGCAGCCUGGAAAGGAUAAAUGAAUAUUAGACUAAGAUUUGUUUUCCAGGAGGCUCAAUCUGAACACACAGAAUGUCAGAGCUGGAAGGGACUAUAGAGAUCAUCUGAUCUGAUCCUCUUGUACGGAUGAUCGCAAAACUGAGGUGUAGAGAGGGGAAUGGCCAAAAUCACAAAGCAAGUUAGCGUUAAGAGCUGAGACUAGAAUUCAGGGUCCUCACUCCCAGGCCACCGAACCAUGCAGCCCCUUCUUUGGGGGAAGAGACCUGUGUCAGUCUUGGUUAAUUGUUCCAGGGAACCUUGCUAACAGAAACUUGCUCUUGCCUUGGCUCUUCAGUAGAUGACCUGGCUGUAAAGAGAUUCCCUGGACGAGCCAGAUCAUUCAGUUUCAGCGAGUCCUUGAGCUCCACAACAUCUACCAGAUAUAGCAGACAAGCACCCAUGGAGGCAGGUUUCGGGCCUGAAGCAGAUCAGAGGGCUUUGCAAAAGACAGCAUAGAGCCAUCUUCCUGCAACUUUACCUCUUUCCCUCAGAUGGGGAGCCAUGACUGGGUUGCACCUCAGGAUACUGUAAUUUGACUCCAUAAUUGCUUUUGCUCCUGAAACCUGGGAAUCAAUGGAAAGGCAGGGAAUGUGCCUCUUCUGUGGCCAGAUUCUGUUAUUUGCAAUUAAAGCAAGUUUUUAAAAAAUGCAAGAGGCAGUUGUUAGUCUUCAGGGCUUGGCAACUGAAAUAGCUAUGUGGCGGAUACGGAAAACAGAGGACAAUUUGAGGAUCUUGCUGGAAUAAUAAAUGACAGCUACCAUUUGUUGAGCACCUAUUAUAUAUCAGGCACUGAGCUGGGUAGGCUCUAAACUUCACAAUAACCCUGUGACUUAACUACUUUAUCUCCAUUUUGUAGUUGAAGAAAUAAGUUCAGAGAGAAAGAUUCCUUCCCAAGGUCAUGCAGCUAGUAAAUGAUAGAAUCAGGAUUCAUAGCAUCACUAUAGGGGGUCAAUAUUUACACAAAAAAGGAAAGUCACAAGCCUGUUUAAAAUGAAGUGACCACCUUUUCUUGCAUAGACUAAAUAACUCGAACUGGCAUUUUUAGGUUGGAAAGACAGCUGAAUUAGUAGUUAAGUCUGAUAGCCAAGUAAGUUUUAAAAACCAAAGCAUCCAGGAUGCACACCCCUGCACCAUUUGCUGUGCGAAUUAAUAGUUCUGUCUCUCUCUCUCUUUCUUUUUUCUUUUUAUUCUUUGAGAUGGAUUUUCGCUCUUGUCGCCCAGGCUGGAGUACAAUGGCACGAUCUUGGCUCACUGCAACCUCCGCCUCCCGGGUUCAAGCGAUUCUUCUGCUGGGAUUACAGCAUAUGCCACCAUGCCCAGAUUAUUUUUUUGUAUUUGUAGUAGAGACGGGGUUUCACCAUGUCAGUCAGGCUGGUCUUGAACUCCUGACCUCAGGUGAUCCACCCGCCUCAGCCUCCCACACUGCUGGGAUUACAGGCAUGAGCCACCGCUCCUGGCCUCUCUUUCUUUUUUAAACAAAGAACUUUGCACUUGGCCAGAGAGGAGGAGAAAGCCCAUUUUCUCCCUUCCUAAGCUAGAUCCAAAUAAAAGAAAGUUCAGUUUUCCCCCAUAACUAUUCUUGGGUCAUGAACUUUGAUCUGGAGUUUGUUUUGUUUCAGGAAUGUGUGCACCCAGCUUGCUGAUCCAACAAAGUCUAUUGCUUACCAGUCUAGCUUGAUGAAGCCUUUUGGCCAGAAGUCAAUUUGUUUUGGAUCAGAGAAAUUUCCUGACAAGGUAUAUUUGUUUUCUAGUGACAGAAAGGCAAAGGAACAAGUCCUAGUUGUUGUUGUUGUUGUUGAAUACUAAAUUUAAGAUAUGUCAGCUUGCUUUCAAUGAGCCUUGGGCUUCUGUUAUUGCUUGAGCAUUUGGAACUCGAGCUUCCAGAGAAAUUUGAGGUCCUCGCUUGUUCUCUGCCUUCAAGAAACAAUGACCUGAUUCUGUCUUUAAAAAAAAAAAUCUCAGAAUUCUUUUUUUGUUUGUGUUUUUUUUUUUUUUUGAGACAGAGUCUCACUCUGUUGCCCAGGCUGGAGUGCAGUGGCGCCAUCUCGGCUCACUGCAACCUCCGCCUCCCAGGUUCAAGCAAUUCUCCUGCCUCAGCCUCCCAGGUAGCUGCCACUACAGGUGCUGCACCACCACGCCCGGCUAAUUUUUGUAUUUUUAGUAGAGACAGGGUUUCACCAUAUUAGCCAGGUGGGUCUUGAACUCCUGACCUUGUGAUCCACCCGCCUCGGCCUCCCAAAGUGCUGGGAUUACAGGCGUGAGCCACCUUGCCUGGCCAAAAAUCUCAGAAUUCUUUAAGACUGUUUUAAUUGCUCCAUCAGUAAUUUUGAAGCACUUUCCUUUUUUUUUUUUUUUCCCCUUUUUGUCCCUUUCCCCAAGCCACCAAUUGGAUGGAUGAAUGUUUGACGGGGAAGAGGAAGGGUAGGAGGAUGCAUGGAUGAGUGGAUGAGUGGAUCGAUGGAUGUAUUGAUAAAUAGAUAGAACCAGUCAUCUGAAGCAACUUAAGAAUUGUAGCCUUGACUCCUUGAGACUGUAGAUUUCGAUCCAGGAAACAUUUAUUUAGCACCUGCCAGAUGCCAGAAAUUUAUACCAUUUAAAACUCAGUAAGUCUUUUAAAUAUCAGGAAGGAGAGAAGCGACAUCAUGAUACAUCCUAUGGGUAUUAAAAAGCCAAUAGAAUAUUAUGAAUAAUUUUAUGCUAAUAAAUUUAACAACUUCAACAUCAUAAACAAAUUCCUUGAAAAAUAAAAAGUACCAAAAUUCAUUCAAGAAGAAAUAGAUACCAGCCUGAGCAACAUGGCAAAAUCCCAUCUCUACAAAACAUCAAAAAAAAAAAAAAUUAGUCGGGCAUGGUGGUGCACACCUGUAAUCCCAGCUUGUCAGGAGGCUGAAGUGGGAGGAUCACCUGAGCCCAGGGAGGUCAAGGAUGCAGUGAGCCAUGGUCUCACCACUGCACUCUAGCCUGGGUGACAGAAUGAGACCCCGUCUCAAAAAAAAAGAAGAAGUAGAUAAUCUGAAUAGCCCUAUAUCUAUAGAAACUUAAUAGUGCUGGGAGAUAUAGGUAUUAUUAUCCUCAUUUUACAGAUGUGAAAAUUGAGGCUCAGAGAAGUAAAGUCUAUUGCUCAAGGUCAUGUGGCUAGAAUAUGGCAGAGCCAUGAUUCAGAUCCAGGUCUUCUGAUUCUUAUUCCAGUGUCCUUUCUAGCAUACCAUGUUGCCUCUAAAGAUUGCAGCUCCUUAUUUACUAGAAAAUUGUUCCUGCCCAAUCUACAUCUCCACCUCACCCCAUCUUUUCUUAAGCACUAUGUUUGUGUUUUUAUCAGUAUUAUAUUCAUUGUCUUUGGAAUACAUGUUCUUGUUUGUGUUUGGAAAAAAAAUCUCUUUUACCAGCUUGCACUCGGACCAACUUGGAAAAAAAAAAGCUUAAAUGUUUUUGCUAUGUACAGUUUAAAAAUGUGAAGUUUGUAGCUUUAACUUUUUGUAAGAAAAUCUAAUAACACUGGCUUAAGUGCUGACUUGAAAUGCUAUUUUGUAAGGUUUGGAUGUAAGUAAUCAAUUGAGGUCAGCAGUUUGUAUGAGACAUAGCUUCCUCCAUUGCCCCCACUCCUUUUUUCUUUUUUAAGUUUGAGAUGCUUCCUGUGUUUUUAUGUUAGAAUUGUUGUUCUCCUUCUUUUCUUCUUCCUAUACCUCAUCACGUUUGUUUUAAAUAAACUGUCCUUUGGACCACAAACCCUUAUUAACGAGAACCUCAAUAUAUAGCCUGGAUAAUGGUGUUGUGAACAAUCUUUGUGACAUUGA